AGAGCCUCGUCGAUACUACCUGCGGCGCCUCCCUCCACGCCGGUGGGAGCCCGGCUCUGGCUUCUUCAGCGGAGGUGGGAUGGAGUGACUGGGGGGUGCAGGGCUCGGCUCAGUGUCCAGCUGGUGUCUGGCACCCGUGGCUCGCCCUGGGGUCUGGGGGGUGGGGUCUGUGCACGGAUGAAGAAUUCAGGGUCACCUGGCCCAGUUUCCAGUAGCUGUGGCUGCCAGAGUGUUGGUAGGGGAACAGGACCCGUCUUCUCUAACCUCUUAUUGUUGGAAAAAAUCACCCAAAACAAACUUUGCAGGAGGAAGUAUUCACAGCAGCUUUAUCUGGGGGUUUUCCCGUCUCCUUGCCCAAAACUUCCUUUAGGCUUAGGGGGUCCUUCCUGGUGCAAAACCCCUUCCCCCAGCCGGCCCCUGGCUGAACCUGGGCCGGUGCCUGGGCUCCGACCCUGUCUUCCCUGCCCCCACAUUCAUCCUGUUCGCUGGGCCCCAGGGGCCUGAGGUAGGGGCCGGGGUGGGGGGUGGAAAGUGCUGAGAGGGGAAGCAGCUUCUUCCUUCUCUUCCUGCCUCCUGGGACCACCACACCCCCUCAGACAAGGCCUGCGUAAGUGGUUGUCUCUCAAGCUCUGCCCCCUCCCCAGGAAUGGGGGUGGGGCAGGGCUGGGCCAAACUGAGGAAGGUGGGGGGAGUGGUUGUUCUUGUCUUUUUUUUUUUGCCUCUACCCCAUCCCCCACAUUACUUAGCUGGCUGGUUAUUGAGGCAGAAGCGCAUGAGGCUGUGGGACUUGCCUUCCAUUUGAUUUCUGAAUUGUGAAGGUGCAUGCUUUCUGGAGGCCUGCACAGACCUUUCCCACCCGCUUUCCUGAAAGAAUUUGACAGGGAAAGUGAGACCGCAGGAAGGCUUUUUGGGGGAAGGUUUCUUCAAUGCUAGACUCUCUCAGGCAGAGCUGCAUCGGGCCCCCUGCCUUCCCUGCUCCCAAUUUCCUGAGACCGCCCCCCCCCACCCAGAAUUGGGGAUCUUGAUCAGGGUUUGUACCCCGGUUUAAAAAAAAAAUCUGAAAUGUGGUCUUUUUGCAGGAUUUGGAGCCCAGCCUCGUUGGGGAACAGAGAGAGAAUACAACAGUUGGGUUCUCUCUCAGUCCUGGGGGUGGGAGAAAGAUUGUGGGGGGCGGGGAUCGAGAGUGCUUGGAGGGGAAGAGUCUACCACCUCUUUCUUUGUUGUAGAUGGGGGAGUGAGGCUGGGGGCCCAGACUCAGCCCCUUUAUCCUGGGUGGGGAUCACGCUCAGCCCUGUGCUAGGGGGAAGUCAGUGUGGGAACUCAGAUCCUUUUCUGCCGGGGGAUGGGAUUCUGCACCUCUGGGGAGCAACAGGAGCAGGGAGUUUGGGCAAAAAUAACCUGCUUUCCCUCUUCUCUGUGCCAAGGUGGAGGAGGGGAGGGCAUUGUAAUUAUGUUGGCUACAUGAUUAGUUUAGCUAAUCUGGUUUGUGGCUGUGAUGAAAAGAUAAUACUGAGGAAGUACUGCUAGGAGGUGCUUGGUGAAAACUGGCCACUGACUGGACUGGGGGAUGCGGGGGAGGAGGAGAAGGUAGGACCCAGUUAGUCAUUUCUUGCUAGAUCAAGCCCCAGCUUGGGUGACUUGAGCCCUCCCACCCCCACUCCACCCCUCCCUUGCACCCUGGCUCCACCCCAUUCCCUCUGGAGCCUCUGUUUGGGCUGCCAGGGCCGAGGCUUUGAGAAUGCAGUGCAUAGGAACGAAAAAGGUCGGGCUAGGGCUGCCAACCUUUUUCCCAUCCUGGAGCCACCUUAGAGUGAGAUGGGUCAAUUGACUAGUCUACAGAAGGACUGUUUAUUUGGAGAGAUGGGACAGUGGGGCAGUUCUGAGCACAGGGCUUUGGGCUUGAACUGAGCUGGGUUUGAGACCCAGCUCUGUCUCUCAUUACCUGAGCCUCAGUGACCUCUUUGGCAAAAUGGGAAUACUAAUACCUAUCUACCCAUAGCCACGAUGGAGGUGAUGAACCUGAUGGAGCAGCCUAUCAAGGUGACUGAGUGGCAGCAGACAUACACCUACGACUCGGGUAUCCACUCGGGCGCCAACACCUGCGUGCCCUCCGUCAGCAGCAAGGGCAUCAUGGAGGAGGAUGAGGCCUGCGGGCGCCAGUACACGCUCAAGAAAACCACCACUUACACCCAGGGGGUGCCCCCCAGCCAAGGUGAUCUGGAGUACCAGAUGUCCACAACAGCCAGGGCCAAACGGGUGCGGGAGGCCAUGUGCCCUGGUGUGUCAGGCGAGGACAGCUCGCUUCUGCUGGCCACCCAGGUGGAGGGGCAGGCCACCAACCUGCAGCGACUGGCCGAGCCGUCCCAGCUGCUCAAGUCGGCCAUUGUGCAUCUCAUCAACUACCAGGACGAUGCCGAGCUGGCCACUCGCGCCCUGCCCGAGCUCACCAAACUGCUCAACGACGAGGACCCGGUGGUGGUGACCAAGGCGGCCAUGAUUGUGAACCAGCUGUCGAAGAAGGAGGCGUCGCGGCGGGCCCUGAUGGGCUCGCCCCAGCUGGUGGCCGCUGUCGUGCGUACCAUGCAGAAUACCAGCGACCUGGACACAGCCCGCUGCACCACCAGCAUCCUGCACAACCUCUCCCACCACCGGGAGGGGCUGCUCGCCAUCUUCAAGUCGGGUGGCAUCCCUGCUCUGGUCCGCAUGCUCAGCUCCCCUGUGGAGUCGGUCCUGUUCUAUGCCAUCACCACGCUGCACAACCUGCUCCUGUACCAGGAGGGCGCCAAGAUGGCCGUGCGCCUGGCCGACGGGCUGCAAAAGAUGGUGCCCCUGCUCAACAAGAACAACCCCAAGUUCCUGGCCAUCACCACCGACUGCCUGCAGCUCCUGGCCUACGGCAACCAGGAGAGCAAGCUGAUCAUCCUGGCCAAUGGUGGGCCCCAGGCCCUCGUGCAGAUCAUGCGUAACUACAGUUAUGAAAAGCUGCUCUGGACCACCAGUCGUGUGCUCAAGGUGCUAUCCGUGUGUCCCAGCAAUAAGCCUGCCAUUGUGGAGGCUGGUGGGAUGCAGGCCCUGGGCAAGCACCUGACCAGCAACAGCCCCCGCCUGGUGCAGAACUGCCUGUGGACCCUGCGCAACCUCUCAGAUGUGGCCACCAAGCAGGAGGGCCUGGAGAGUGUGCUGAAGAUUCUGGUGAAUCAGCUGAGUGUGGAUGACGUCAACGUCCUCACCUGUGCCACGGGCACACUCUCCAACCUGACAUGCAACAACAGCAAGAACAAGACGCUGGUGACACAGAACAGCGGUGUGGAGGCUCUCAUCCAUGCCAUCCUGCGUGCUGGUGACAAGGACGACAUCACGGAGCCUGCCGUCUGCGCUCUGCGCCACCUCACUAGCCGCCACCCUGAGGCCGAGAUGGCCCAGAACUCUGUGCGUCUCAACUAUGGCAUCCCAGCCAUCGUGAAGCUGCUCAACCAGCCCAACCAGUGGCCACUGGUCAAGGCAACCAUCGGCUUGAUCAGGAAUCUGGCCCUGUGCCCAGCCAACCAUGCCCCGCUGCAGGAGGCAGCGGUCAUCCCCCGCCUCGUCCAACUGCUGGUGAAGGCCCACCAGGAUGCCCAGCGCCACGUAGCUGCAGGCACACAGCAGCCCUACACGGAUGGUGUGAGGAUGGAGGAGAUUGUGGAGGGCUGCACCGGAGCACUGCACAUCCUCGCCCGGGACCCCAUGAACCGCAUGGAGAUCUUCCGGCUCAACACCAUUCCCCUGUUUGUGCAGCUCCUGUACUCGUCGGUGGAGAACAUCCAGCGCGUGGCUGCCGGGGUGCUGUGUGAGCUGGCCCAGGACAAGGAGGCGGCCGACGCCAUUGAUGCAGAGGGGGCCUCGGCCCCACUCAUGGAGUUGCUGCACUCCCGCAACGAGGGCACUGCCACCUACGCUGCUGCCGUCCUGUUCCGCAUCUCCGAGGACAAGAACCCAGACUACCGGAAGCGCGUGUCCGUGGAGCUCACCAACUCCCUCUUCAAGCAUGACCCGGCUGCCUGGGAGGCUGCCCAGAGCAUGAUUCCCAUCAAUGAGCCCUAUGGAGAUGACAUGGAUGCCACCUACCGCCCCAUGUACUCCAGCGAUGUGCCCCUUGACCCGCUGGAGAUGCACAUGGACAUGGAUGGAGACUACCCCAUCGACACCUACAGCGACGGCCUCAGGCCCCCGUACCCCACUGCAGACCACAUGCUGGCCUAGGCGGCCUGGCCCCAGUGCGGUUCCUCAUCUGAGAGGCUCUCCGUGCAGGCGAUGGGGCAAGACAGAAAAGUGCCUGAGCUGGGGAAGCCGGGGUGUAACUUCCUGCUGCACCCUGCGCCUCCAGAGGUCCUCCGUAGGGUCUUUCUUGGGAUAGUGUUCUGCUCCUGCUUUUCUGUCCUGGGCAUGGGUCCAGGGCCUGACACCCCCUCCCCGCCCCUGUGGCCCUGGCCACUAAAGCUUCAGACUCAAGUACCCAUUCUGUUUUCCCCCAGCAACGCCCCUCCAAACCUCCAGCCUCCCUGUCUCCAGCUGCCUGGGCCCGGAAGGGCUUUGGUUCCUUCUCUGGGUCUGAUUUUCUCACUGAACUCCACCGACCAACUGCCCUAAGCCCCCAGGGCCUCCAGGGCCCAGGUUCGAGACCCAAACCCCCAAAAUCCAAAACUUCUCUUGAAAAGUUCAGGGACCGUCCAGGGGAGAUGGGGAGGAGAUAUGGAGUGAGUCACCUGCUCCAGAAGAUGCCAGCUUCUCUCUCCAGGGUGCUUAGUUGGCUUUGCCCACCCCUCACUCCCCAGGGAGCUCUGGGGACAGCUUCCUCACACCCCUGUCCCACCCACACAGCUGCCCUAGCUGACCCCGAGAAGUGCUCUUGGCUGACCCCUCUGGUGUGUGGUGAGGGGCUUUCUCUUCCCCUUCCUGUUUCAGACCCCCCCAUUUCCCGCACAUGGUGUGGGGGGCUGGGGGAGGUCCAAGCAGAGUGUUUUAUUAUUAUCGCUUUAUGUUUUUGGUUAUUGGUUUUUUUGUAUAGACCAAAGCAAAGAAAAUAAAAAUAACACAGAUG